UCUGUAAAACAGAAAGAGACAGGAGAUAAGCAUGACAAAAUAUAGGGAAGAAAUGACUUUUGCCUAAACUUCCAAAUUGUGUACAAUUGAAGCCUCUGCUUUAUAGCUCUUAGCACACCUCUCAAAUAAGAAGGCAGUACUGGGAAGGCUCUGAACCUGUGGCAGAACCACUGAUAGCUGUGGAGCUAUUCCAAGGAGUCUGGGAAUCAGGGGGAUUAUCAAGAUCAUUGUUAGAAUAAAUUAAUCUUACUGUAUAUAUAGCAGAAGUUUUCAAGCAUAUGUAAAUGCUACUAAUAACCAAAUAAUUACACCUUGUUUUUCUUUAAACUGUAACUCUCAAGUAUGUCUCUACAUAAUUUUUUGAUGGUAGUGUCUGCAUGCUCAAAAAGCUUGAAAACACUACUGGAGAAGAAGGUCUCGGGAGUGUGAUGAAAUACGUUUACAUGGCAGCUUCAUCAUUUAAUUGGUGAAAGUGACUAUGUGUCUUAAACUCUCUGAGCCUCAGUUUGCACAUCCAAAAGCAAGGAUAUAAUGCCAUGAACCUUUCCACCUCAAGUCCACAAGGCAGAAUAGCAAGAUGUUAACUGCCACUCUGAGGACCACCAAAUAAAAGGACAAUUUAUUAGGCCACUUGCCAGCAUGGACACAAUCGACUCUUGGCAUUUCUUAUUAUCCACAGAAAAAUUAAAAGUAUAAAUGUAGAACAAAAUUAUCGUGUUUUUUUUAAUAGUAACAUGUAAGAUCAAUCUUUGUCUUUAAAAUACCGUGUAUCUCAUUCUUGGAAAGCGUCAAAAUGAAAAUGGUAUAGUAAGUUUUACCUACAACUUGAAUUAAAAUUAUUCUUGAAAUAUGUUCUGAAUGGUUAGAUGAAAUGGUAAUUAAAUACAAAUAGAGAUAAUCAUAUACUCUCUCUCCAUAAGGCUCCCACCUCCUUCAAUGAAGUCUAGUUCACCUAAAAUGACACUAUUAACAUUAAUUCAAUAUUCUAAGUUGAUAAGCACAUUAAAUCAAAACACAGCAAGAUUAUUUUAAGAGUCUGACUGAAAUGUCAGGAUGAGAAAUAGAUUAAUAAAUAUUGGCUUCUAAUGUUGGUAAUGAAAACAAACACGUUAUUUUCAGAAAAUAAAAGGUCUUCGCCAUUAGGUACAAAUCAUAAAGGGAUUAUCUACAGUUACUACACUGUAACAACUUUUUACAUAUUGUAUUAUAGAACAAGCUUUUGAGAAGACAAAGCAACACAUCAGCAGUUUAACCAAUUGUCUUUCUCUUUUAACAGGCUGGUCUACAUUAGAUUAGAUAUAAAAGGCCCAGGUAUUACUUGUGUUCGAUCUUAGCCAAAUGGCUGAGAAACAUCCAGGUACAUUUAAGUCAGUGACAAAAGAAAACACUAUCCCUUAGUAAAAUUACAUAAAAUAGGAAACAUCUCUUACUUUAAGAGCAACCAUGGUACUUGUUCCUAUGGUGAAAACUGAUGUUAUCUCGAUUAGUUAAUUAUUCAUCCCAACACCUGGUCUUGCUCCCUUUUCCACCUCUAGCUAUGUUAACAAUAGAGUUCAGUAAUUUGCUGAUAAAGAAUCUUAACUGCAGUAUCUAACAGACCUUAGUGAUUAAGCAUAUGACUUACCCUUUGUACAGAAGUAAACUGAGGCCAAAAGAACUGAGGUAUCUUAUUAAAAAUCAGAGAGCUAGUUAGUUGAAAAGUCCACCUGUCCUUCCUUUCCACAUGUCUCACCAGAAAAACAGCAAUGGUGAAAAGUCAACUCUGUUUUUAAUGGGCCACUUUGUAUAUUUUAACUGUUAAAAUAAUCCAAGAGGAUAGUAGUCAUAUACGAAGAUCCUUUAGAUAUAAUGUGUAGGACCAGCAUUAAUUUAAUCAACCAAGUCUCCUCUCAUUGAAUUGUUAAUUCAUAAUUACAAAGAUGACAUUACAGUAAAUUAAGAAAUACUGUAAUUUCAUUCUCUCCAAAAAGUAUACAUUGAAGUUUGGUGAAUACUGUUAUAUUUUCAACUAAUAAAUCAAUGUGCCAAUUCUGGGUCUUAGGCAUAUUGUAUAUACUGGAAUGAUAUUCACUUUAAUUAAAUUUGUUUUGAGAUGUAGAAUGUAAUACAGAUCCUACGUGUUUUUAAAAGUUCACAUCAAUUUCAAGCUUUUAAAAAUGUAUGUACACAAGAAAGCUUCUUUUGCAAUUUAUAUGUUUACAAAUGUUGCCAUUAGCUAAGCUAUAUUUUGGAAUGUGAUCAAACAAUAUUGAAUGUCAAGUCUUAACAGCAGGGCUGGUCUAAGGAAUUCCCUCUAAGCUAAAUCUGAUCCUUUCAUAUGUGGCUACUGCUCUUUUAAACUACUGUAUCCCUAAAGGGCUAAAAGGAAGAAAAUCCUAACUUAAUAAGUGAAGGCAGCAAGGCAUAGUAUUUGAAUGGCUACCUUUCAUUUUAACUCUACUUCUUAAAUUCAAAAUUGGAUUUGGGUUUGUUUCAAGUUGUUCACAAUUUACUAACGAAAUGUGCAUCUCUCAUUCUUCCCCCAAAAGAAAGAAGUCAUCCACUCCAGCUACAUAUAAGUCUCCAAUUUCUGUCUUACAACUAAACGUGAAAACCGAAAUACCACUCAUUGAAAAAAAAAAUGUACAGAGAAUUGGCAGGCUGCAUGUUUAUGUGAACCUUCAGAAAACAUGGAAACACGCAGCCCCAACUCACCAGGAAAAUCAACACUUGUGAUCAAACUAUUUUGUGACAUUUUAUGUCUUUUAUACAUUUCACUUCAUAUCCAGUAUUCCAGUUUUGCACCGGCUUGCCUGUAUCAACCCCAAAUCGCCUGAGAGCAAUCUAGUACUGUAGCAGAACCGUUUCAACAUGAAGAGUUCUGCUCAUCGCCUGUGGCGUGGUCUUCGAAACACCUGAAUCAAACAUUGAUUCCCCUCUCCCUGCUAUUUAAAACCGAGGGACGUCAGGCUUGGGUUGUAGGUAAAGAAAAGCCACAGUAAUCAAACAAGCAACCAAAAUACCCGAACACGGAACACGCUAAGAACAAAGGAAACACAAGAGUGUGAACAGGAAAUGAAGCAACUCUACACCCAUAAAUACCUUCUGGGGCCGCCAACAUAGGUAAAAGUAAAGGUGGAGUCUGAGUAUCUGAAAUCUGAAACAGAAAGUCCUGUCAAAAGCUACCCCUGGAGUGGAUUUGUUUUAACCCCGAUCAGGACUUGGGCCCUCCAUUUGGUGGAGUCAGGGGAGGCCUGGCCGGGCGGGAGGCGAGGGCUAGAGGGCGGCGAGGUCUCUCCGCGCAGCGUCCGAGGGGAUGCGGCGCGCCCCCGACUGGGUGCAGCGGCAGGCCGCCCCCGGCAGCAAGUGCCGGGUGCCAUGGCAACGGCGGGAAUUUCCCGGUCGGGGAGGCCGGAAGCAGCCCCAGCCGGGCUCGCGGCAGCGAAAGCAAAAUCCGAUCUCUCUCCCGGGGGAGCAAAAUGGACGAAAGGCGACCCCCCAGGCAGGGGCGCUGGGUGCCUUGGGAAUCCGAGGAAUCCCUUCUCUUUGCCAGUCGGAGGGGACUAGAUGGAGCCGAAGGGGCCGGAGAUGGGCCGAGCGCUGCCCCCCGGGGGUCCUCGGCGCCGGGCGCAGCUUAGGAGCGCAGCGCAGCAGGCUCCAUUCCCGGCCGCCGCCGCUCAGCCCAUUACGCAAACCUGGCGGGUCCAACCAACCCCGCUCUGCCGCCGCUGCUGGAACCCAGGAGGCGUGCUUGCAGGCUUCGGGCACUACGCGGGGCUGGAAAUACCACGCACUGCCCCUUCGCCUAGACCCCCGCUCGGGCCACGCGGGUUCUGCCCUCAAAGCUGCCACACACGUCGCGGUCGGAGAACUGAGAAAGGGGCGCUGGGUCCGAGGUUCUGGAAAAGCAAGAACUCACCUGCAAACAGGCAGUCCUCAGCUCUGGACUUCUGGAUCACGACGUCGAUAUCCUUCUGAAUUCGGUCUUGCCUUGAACACAUCCCCAUUAAAUAAAUCCUUGGAAAAGAAGCAGCCGCUAUUUCCACCCCACCCCCCUCGCACGCUUUCAGCUUUCGUAAAUAUUCAGUUAAAAAUGAAACCUCUGGCCGAGGCAGGGGCUGAAGGCCAAGUGGUUUUGGAAGUGAUCCUGGGUGAGAGGAGGAGGAGGAGGAGGAGGAGGAGGAGGAGGAGGUGGAGGAGGAGGGGGAGGUCGGCUUUCCAUUUCCAGAUGUUACCGUCCAGCUGCUGCUCGCCGCUGCUGGAUUCCAGUUUCCUCCCCUUCUGGCGAUGGAUUGGUGAUGACACCGAGUCUCACUUUCUCCUUCCCCCGCCCGGACCAACCGCCGUGGGGGGCCGAGGGUGCCGGGGACGGCCGGAGAGCGAUCACCGGCUGGGCGGCGGGAGCCGACGAGGGGCGAGCCCCGCUCCGGCUCAAGCGCGCACACCCCUCACGGCCCGCACUCCGGCCUUCCACACCCGUGCACACUCUCGCCCGCGGGCGGCGGCAGCCGUGCCCAGGCUGCUGCAGCGCCACCCGCCCGCCGCGGACCCUCCGCGCCCUCCGCCUAGUCACCCGGCCCGGCCGCGGGCCGCCGGGGCUCGCAGAGUGUCAGCCAUCCCGGGCAGGAGUCGCGUCUCCCCACCCCGACCUCCACUCGCGCCGGGAGCUGAGCGGCAGUGUAGGUAGUGAAGACUCCCUGGGGCUCCCAGCCUUCCCUCUCCGCGCUCUCCCCCCGUCACUUUUAUGAAUUCGACUCCACUUUCUAAAGGAAUUAUGAGUCUUGUGGCAAACACAAACCGGAGUGGCCGGGAGGGGGAAAAGGGGGGAAAAGAAAAUCUUUAAAAAUUAAAAAAAUAAUAAAACGAACAAAUCUCUACUUGUUGCCACAUCAGAUAACACGGAAAAAGCCUUGAAAUUACUCCAGAUGUGCACCCUCCCCUUCCCUCAGUGCCUGAGUCUUUUUCUUCCAGAUCGAAGUAUUUCAGCCCUUUUGGGGCGCCGUUUGCGAAACACAGCCCCUUUUGAGGGACUUCCUCCUCUUGAAAAGACUCACCAGUUCUCCCUUCCUAGGUGUUUCUGUUCAUGAGAAAUUGUCAGAAUCAACUGGCACGUUCCAGGGUCUUCCUAAAGGAUGGAAACCUGUUUGGCUUGCUUUUUAAAACCACCUCCUUUGACAGUCAGCCCAGGGAAAGCUACAAUCCAGGUUUUCAGAAAUGAGAUACUGCUCUGAUUCUCACUUUCUGUUCUGCCUAAGGACACCUCAGGCUGACGUAGCUGCCCCACCUCUAUAUUGGUUUAUGCCCUAGGAGGGGUCUCCAGCAGGCACUUUUCUUGUUGAUCUUUUCUCCGCUGAGAAGGCUCCCGCCAGUAGACCAUGACUCGUUUUGCUUUGCAUUCUCAGUGCCACGUACAGUGCCUGGAAUACAGGAGGGUGGCCUAAAUGUUGGCUGAAUGCAUGAAUGGUCAUUUCUUGCAGCCUCUUUUCAUUACCCUGUCUCAUCAGCUUUCUUAUCAGAAUAAGUGCCCAAGAGUGCCAAACGGUUUCAGACCCUUAAUCAAUUUAGUUCUGAUUCUGACCGUGACAACAUGAUGUUCAGCACGGUAGGAAUGACUGCCAUCUCUGAAGGAGUCUUAAGAUUCUGUAGAAUCAGUGAAAGAUUCUAUGUUCUAACGCCUUUAUCUUUCAGGAAAGAAAUUACAAAAUAGUUUCAUUGUCCAGUCAUAUUCACUAUGAGUUAUAAGAGGAAACAUUCUAUCUAGAAUUAGAAAUACCAUUUGACCCAGCCAUCCCAUUACUGGGUAUGUACCCAAAGGACUAUAAAUCAUGCUGCUAUAAAGACACAUGCACACGUAUGUUUAUUGCGGCACUAUUCACAAUAGCAAAGACUUGGAACCAACCCAAAUGUCCAACAAUGAUAGACUGGAUUAAGAAAAUGUGGCACAUAUACACCAGGGAAUACUAUGCAGCCAUAAAAAAGGAUGAGUUCAUGUCCUUUGUAGGGACAUAGAUGAAAUUGGAAAUCAUCAUUCUCAGUAAACUAUCGCAAGAACAAAAAACCAAACACCGCAUAUUCUCACUUAUAGGUGGGAAUUGAACAAUGAGAACACAUGGACACAGGAAGGGGAACAUCACACUCUGGGGACUGUUGUGGGUUGUGGGGAGGGGGGAGGGAUAUCACUGGGAGAUAUACCUAAUGCUAGAUGACGAGUUAGUGGGUGCAGCGCACCAGCAUGGCGCAUGUAUGCAUAUGUAACUAACCUGCACAUUGUGCACAUGUACCCUAAAACUUAAAGUAUAAUAAUAAUAAAUUUAAAAAAAAGAACAAAACAUCACAUUGUACCACAUAAAAAAAAAAAAGUUGGAUUUUGCAAGGAAGAUAGACAUCUGAAUAAAGUUUGGCCAAGCAAGGAAUCUUUGUUAGUACUACUUCUUGUUUAAGGAAAGAAGAGACACUCAUCUUUCCUUCAAACAAUAUAAGUCUCUUUUCUUGUUUGAUCACCUUUUAUUCAUUAAGAACCAGUUGAAUCAUCUGUUGGGACUUGGUAGCAGAGGAUAUUUCCUGGAUAGUGUGAGCUAUCAAGCCUUUAAUGUGGGAAGUUUAGUUUCUAUAAAAAUAAAAUUAAAAAAGAUUAAUAGUUGGAACGAACUAUAAAGACAGUUUCUGAGCCCAGAGGGCAGCUGAUCAAUAAGAUUUCUAGAUGCUGGGCUUGUAGUAUCUUCAGCUGGAGUGAGAAGAGGCAUUGGAUUAGUUUGCAGUUUGAAUGCCAUAAAGAUGGGCCACACACAAGCUGUUGUGGUAAUUUUUCUGAAGCUUAUGUCAAGUCAUCCAGUUUCAGUUUGAAGGACUUCAAGAAAUGAAAAGUUUAUAAUUUUAGUGAUUCCAAGCCAGAAUAGCAG